GGGGCCCACUCCCGAGCGCAGGCGGGCAGCCAGGCGGGCGGCGCGGCGCGGGCCGGCAGGAAGCGUAUUCUGGGCACGGGGCGCCGGGCGGGCCGGCUGCGCCGAGCGGCAGUGGUGGGAUACCACCCAAGGCCUCGCGCGGCGCCGCCCGUCGAGGGGCGGGCGGCGGCGUAGCCACUGGGCCGUCGAAGAGCGCAGGAGGCCGGUGGGCCGGGCCGGGCCGCGCGGCGCAGCCAUGCCUGGCUUUACGUGCUGCGUGCCAGGCUGCUACAACAACUCGCACCGGGACAAGGCGCUGCACUUCUACACGUUUCCAAAGGACGCUGAGUUGCGGCGCCUCUGGCUCAAGAACGUGUCGCGUGCCGGCGUCAGUGGGUGCUUCUCCACCUUCCAGCCCACCACAGGCCACCGUCUCUGCAGCGUUCACUUCCAGGGCGGCCGCAAGACCUACACGGUACGCGUCCCCACCAUCUUCCCGCUGCGCGGCGUCAAUGAGCGCAAAGUAGCGCGCAGACCCGCUGGGGCCGCGGCCGCCCGCCGCAGGCAGCAGCAGCAACAGCAGCAGCAGCAGCAACAGCAGCAACAGCAGCAGCAGCAGCAACAGCAGCAGCAGCAGCAGCAGCAGCAGCAGUCCUCACCCUCUGCCUCCACUGCCCAGACUGCCCAGCUGCAGCCGAACCUGGUAUCUGCUUCCGCGGCCGUGCUUCUCACCCUUCAGGCCACUGUAGACAGCAGUCAGGCUCCGGGAUCCGUACAGCCGGCGCCCAUCACUCCCACUGGAGAAGACGUGAAGCCCAUCGAUCUCACAGUGCAAGUGGAGUUUGCAGCCGCAGAGGGCGCAGCCGCUGCGGCCGCCGCGUCGGAGUUACAGGCUGCUACCGCAGGGCUGGAGGCUGCCGAGUGCCCUAUGGGCCCCCAGUUGGUGGUGGUAGGGGAAGAGGGCUUCCCUGAUACUGGCUCCGACCAUUCGUACUCCUUGUCGUCAGGCACCACGGAGGAGGAGCUCCUGCGCAAGCUGAAUGAGCAGCGGGACAUCCUGGCUCUGAUGGAAGUGAAGAUGAAAGAGAUGAAAGGCAGCAUUCGCCACCUGCGUCUCACUGAGGCCAAGCUGCGCGAAGAACUGCGUGAGAAGGAUCGGCUGCUUGCCAUGGCUGUCAUCCGCAAGAAGCACGGAAUGUGAACUGGUGCCCCGGCAGCCUGCUGGACUCCCAGACCCCAUCCAGCCAGGGGACCGCAGGCCAUUGUUGAACUCCUCUAUACUCCUGGGCACUGGUUGACAGUACUGAGGCUUAAGGCAGCUGGACUCUCUUGCUGGUGACCUGGCAUCCUCAAUUGUUUCCUCCUGAAGUGGAAGCUGGGGCCUUAGACUCUGCCCUGGUGACACCAGCAAUUAUGACUUUGUCUACCCUUCCUCCCCAGUUAUUGUUGCAGAUUCUGGUUAAGCAGAGGCUUCAGAACCACUGAACUUGAAACUUACCCUCUAGGGAUGCAGGUGGGAUGUCCAGGGACUAUAGGUUUGGGAAAACCAUACCUUAAGGUUGGUCAGCAGUCAGACAACUCUAAUGUGUGUAGUGAUAAGAGAUUCAAGUAACAUCAGUUCUCCUCCUUUUCAUGCUUUUCCUUCCCAGGUGCAGCCUGUGAUUCUGAUGGGGACUGGUAAAUCUGUGCCUCUGCCUCCUAGGACUUAUUUUCCCAGGAGGCCAUUUACAAGGGGAUCUGGAUGACCUGCUGAUGGAGAUCCAGCUUGCCAGGGACUUAGGUUUAUCCUGUUUUGUUUGCUACUGGUUACAAAUUCUAUUUUCUGUACAAUUAGUCAGACUAAAGUUUUCACUGUGUUUGUUUGGCAAAACAAAUUAAACAAAAAGUAAGGUUUUUA